AGUUCCCGCGACCCCAACGUCCCAGAGGCGGGGCCGGAGUCGGCGGUGGCGCUCCUUGGAGCCGGCUCCCGCUCCUACCCUGCAAACAGACCUCAGCUCCGCGGAAGUUGCGUGGGUUCCGCCCUCCAGGAGCCUGGAGCAGAUGACGAGAAGGGGAGCUAGUGGGAGAAAUUAAGCAGUCCAUGAAAUCCUUGGGUAUCAUCUGAGCUAAGGUAUGUGAAAGAGGUUUGCAGUCGAUAACGUGCCAUUUAAAGUUGUUUUUACGGUGGGAAUUUCUUGAGGACUGAAACCUUGAAUGCUCGCUCUUGCAUUCCUCACAAUUUCUGGCUCACACUCUGCUACGUAGUAAGGGAUCAGUUAAUGUUUGAAGUUCAUGGACUACUGGAAGUAAAGUGUAAACAGCAAAGUGCGAGAAUGCUAUGCGUGUGAGUACAGACAGUAUAGUACCAUCGCCACGGUGUCUGGGAGAAGGUUUCACAGAGGAAGUGACAUUCGAGUUGGAUUGUGAGGGAUGGCGGGGGUUUACUAGGGCAUUCCAAGUUAAGGGAGGCAUCCUGUGCAGAUAUUGAAACCGGGGCACUGCAAGUAGUUCAGUUUGACUGGAAUGUAGGAUGAGUGGAUGGGGGGGUUAAGGUUGGAAUAAUAGAGUGGGGCUGGAUUGUGAAGAUCCUUUAUUCUGUAUGUAAAGAAGAGCCAUCGGCUUUUUAAAAAAAAUUUAUUUUUAUGUUUAUUUUUGAGACGCAGUUUCACUCUUUGGCCCAGGCUGGAGUGAAGUGGAGUGAUCUCGGCUCACUGCAACCUCCGUCCCCCGGGUUCAAGCGAUUCUCCUGCCUCAGCCUCCCUAGUAGCUGGGAUUACAGGCAAACGCCACCACGCUCGGCUGAUUUUUGUAUUUUUAGUAGAGACGGGGUUUCACCAUGUUGGUCGGGCUGGUCUGGAAAUCCUGACUUCAGGUGAUCCACCCGCCUCGGCCUCCCAAAAUGCUGGGAUUACAAGCGUGAGCCACCGCCCCUGACAUGAGCCAUUGACUUUUAAAGCAGGAGAAUAAUUUGAUCAGAUUUAUAUGGAAACACUCUUCUAGCAGCAUUAUGGGGACUUUUCCAUAAGUCUGGAUACUGAGGAUUUGGAAUUAAAGAAAUCAUUCACCAGACAUCAUGGAGCCUAUAUAUCCUUUUGCACGGCCCCAGAUGAAUACCAGGUUUCCUUCAAGCAGGAUGGUACCUUUCCACUUUCCUCCAUCAAAAUGUGCACUUUGGAACCCAACGCCAACUGGAGAUUUCAUCUACUUACAUCUCAGUUACUACAGAAAUCCAAAGCUUGUGGUGACUGAGAAGACCAUCCGACUUGCUUAUCGUCAUGCUAAGCAGAAUAAAAAAAAUUCGUCAUGCUUUUUACUUGGUUCUCUGACAGCAGACGAAGAUGAAGAAGGUGUAACAUUGACAGUAGAUCGCUUUGAUCCUGGUCGAGAAGUACCUGAAUGCCUAGAAAUAACCCCUACUGCUUCUCUUCCUGGGGACUUUUUGAUUCCAUGCAAAGUUCAUACUCAAGAACUUUGUUCAAGAGAAAUGAUAGUUCACAGUGUAGAUGACUUCAGUUCAGCUUUAAAGGCUCUACAGUGCCAUAUAUGUAGCAAAGAUUCCUUGGACUGUGGUAAGCUGCUUUCCCUAAGAGUUCAUAUCACUUCCAGGGAGAGUUUGGACAGUGUGGAAUUUGACUUGCAUUGGGCAGCAGUAACUCUAGCAAAUAACUUUAAAUGCACACCUGUGAAGCCCAUCCCCAUUAUUCCAACAGCUCUGGCAAGAAACUUGAGCAGUAAUCUGAAUAUUUCUCAAGUUCAAGGGACUUAUAAAUAUGGAUAUCUUACCAUGGAUGAAACACGCAAAUUGUUACUUUUGUUGGAAUCUGAUCCCAAGGUUUAUUCUCUACCAUUGGUGGGAAUUUGGCUGUCUGGAAUUACACAUAUCUAUAGUCCUCAGGUAUGGGCUUGCUGUUUGCGAUACAUAUUCAAUUCUUCUGUUCAAGAAAGGGUUUUUUCAGAAUCUGGAAAUUUCAUCAUAGUUCUCUAUUCUAUGACACAUAAGGAACCUGAGUUUUAUGAAUGCUUCCCUUGUGAUGGCAAGAUACCUGACUUUCGGUUUCAGUUGCUAACCAGUAAGGAAACAUUACAUCUUUUCAAAAAUGUUGAACCUCCUGACAAAAAUCCAAUCCGUUGUGAACUGAGCGCUGAAAGCCAAAAUGCAGAAACAGAGUUUUUCAGUAAGGCUUCCAAGAAUUUUUCAAUUAAGAGGUCUUCCCAAAAGUUAUCUUCUGGGAAGAUGCCAAUACAUGAUCACGACUCUGGUGUUGAAGAUGAAGAUUUUUCUCCAAGACCAAUUCCUAGUCCUCAUCCAGUGAGUCAGAAGAUUUCUAAGAUCCAACCAUCAGUUCCUGAACUUUCACUUGUGUUGGAUGGCAAUUUCAUAGAAUCAAACCCUCUGCCUACUCCAUUGGAAAUGGUGAAUAAUGAAAAUCCUCCUUUGAUUAACCACUUGGAACACUUGAAGCCAUUGCAACCCCAGCUUUAUGAUGAGAAACACAGUCCAGAAGUUGAAGCUGGAGAGCCUUCCUUGAGAGGAAUACCAAAUCAGUUAAACCAGGAUAAACCAGCUCUUUUGAGACACUGCAAAGUAAGACAGCCACCUGCCUAUAAGAAAGGGAACCCCCAUACCAGGAACAGUAUUAAACCAUCUUCUCAUAAUGGGCCAUCUCAUGAUAUAUUUGAAAAGCUCCAAACAGUUUCUGCUGGAAAUGUACAAAACGAAGAGUAUCCUAUAAGACCCUCCACACUUAAUUCUAGGCAGUCUUCUCUUGCCCCGCAGUCCCAACCACACGAUUUUGUUUUUUCACCCCAUAAUUCAGGAAGACCAAUGGAACUUCAGAUACCUACUCCCCCACUGCCAUCUUACUGUUCCACAAACGUUUGCAGGUGUUGUCAGCAUCAUAGUCAUAUUCAAUAUAGUCCGCUAAAUUCUUGGCAAGGAGCAAACACAGUUGGAUCCAUUCAAGAUGUCCAGUCUGAAGCCCUUCAAAAGCAUUCAUUAUUUCACCCAAGUGGAUGUCCAGCCCUGUACUGUAAUGCAUUCUGUUCUUCAAGUAGUCCUAUAGCCUUGAGACCUCAGGGAGAUAUGGGCAGUUGUUCUCCCCACAGCAAUAUUGAACCAUCGCCUGUGGCAAGACCGCCUUCACAUAUGGACUUAUGUAACCCACAGCCUUGCACAGUGUGCAUGCACACACCCAAGACUGAGUCAGAUAAUGGAAUGAUGGGACUAUCUCCAGAUGCAUAUCGGUUCCUCACAGAACAAGACAGACAGCUAAGACUACUUCAGGCACAGAUUCAGCGUUUGUUGGAAGCACAGUCUCUGAUGCCCUGUUCCCCUAAGACAACUGCUGUUGAAGACACAGUGCAAGCUGGAAGACAAAUGGAGUUGGUUUCUGUGGAAGCACAGUCUUCCCCUGGCUUGCACAUGAGAAAAGGUGUAAGCAUUGCUGUGAGCACAGGUGCUAGCUUGUUUUGGAAUGCAGCAGGUGAGGAUCAAGAGCCUGACUCUCAAAUGAAGCAAGAUGAUACCAAAAUUUCCAGUGAGGACAUGAAUUUUUCUGUCGAUAUUAAUAAUGAAGUCACAAGUCUUCCAGGUAGUGCAUCUUCAUUAAAAGCAGUUGAUAUUCCCAGUUUUGAAGAGAGCAACAUUGCUGUGGAAGAAGAAUUUAACCAGCCACUUUCUGUAUCCAACAGCUCUUCUCUAGUUGUGAGAAAAGAACCUGAUGUACCUGUGUUCUUUCCAAGUGGCCAGCUGGCAGAAAGUGUAAGCAUGUGUUUACAGACUGGACCAACAGGGGGUGCCAGUAACAAUUCUGAAACAUCAGAGGAACCAAAAAUUGAGCAUGUAAUGCAACCCUUGCUUCAUCAACCAUCAGAUAACCAGAAAAUUUACCAGGAUUUAUUGGGUCAAGUAAACCACCUAUUAAAUAGUUCCUCCAAGGAAACUGAGCAGCCGUCUACCAAAGCAGUAAUUAUCAGUCAUGAAUGCACCAGAACCCAAAACGUUUACCAUACAAAGAAAAAAACACAUCAUUCAAGACUGGUGGACAAAGAUUGUGUCCUUAAUGCAACUCUUAAGCAACUAAGAAGCCUUGGAGUAAAAAUUGAUUCUCCCACUAAAGUGAAGAAAAAUGCACAUAACGUGGAUCACGCCAGUGUGUUGGCAUGCAUCAGCCCAGAAGCAGUGAUCUCUGGAUUAAACUGCAUGUCAUUUGCUAAUGUUGGCAUGAGCGGCUUAAGCCCCAAUGGUGUGGAUUUGAGCAUGGAGGCAAAUGCUAUAGCUCUGAAAUAUUUAAAUGAAAAUCAGCUGUCACAACUGUCUGUCACUCGAUCGAACCAAAAUAAUUGUGACCCAUUCAGCCUUCUCCAUAUUAAUACAGACAGAAGCACAGUGGGGCUUAGUUUAAUUUCACCAAACAACAUGUCAUUUGCAACCAAAAAAUAUAUGAAGAGAUAUGGACUCCUACAAAGCAGUGACAAUAGUGAAGAUGAAGAGGAACCUCCCGACAAUGCAGAUAGCAAGAGUGAAUAUUUAUUGAAUCAGAACCUUAGGUCCAUACCUGAACAGCUUGGUGGUCAGAAAGAGCCUUCUAAGAAUGACCAUGAAAUAAUUAAUUGUUCUAACUGUGAAUCUGUGGGGACCAACGCAGAUACGCCAGUAUUGAGAAAUAUUACAAAUGAAGUUUUGCAGACAAAAGCAAAACAGCAGUUGACUGAAAAGCCAGCUUUCUUAGUAAAGAACCUUAAACCAAGUCCUGCAGUGAACCUUCGAACCGGGAAAGCAGAGUUCACUCAACAUCCUGAGAAAGAAAAUGAAGGGGACAUUACAAUUUUUCCUGAAAGUUUGCAACCUUCUGAAACGCUAAAGCAGAUGAAUAGCAUGAAUUCAGUAGGCACCUUCUUAGAUGUAAAACGUCUCAGACAGUUACCAAAAUUAUUUUAACCUUUUAACUCCCUGCCCUUUUAAUACAGGGACAGGGUGUCUCCUGAAGAUACUUAGGGAAAACAGGAGCCUACCACAAGGCUCCUGAUCAUUCUGGAGUCACUGUUUCUUGGUAGCAGCCAAUUGGGAAGAGUGACUUCUGUGAGAUGGCUGGCUGGUGAUAGGACUAAGUUCUCAUUGUUCAAAUAGAGCUGUUCAACAUCACUGAAACCUUUAAGAAAAGCCCUGAGAUCAGUUAUUCCUACAAGUUUAAGUAGUAGACAGAUACUAUCCAGCUCUAAGUCUCAACUGCUCUUUUAUACUGUACUUUUUUUUUUGAGACGGAGUUUUGCUCUUGUAGCCCAGGCUGGAGUGCAAUGGCAGGAUCUCAGAUCACUGCAACCUCUGCCUCCUGGGUUCAAGCGAUUUUCCUGCUUCAUCUUCCCAGGUAGCUGGGAUUACAGGCAUGUGCCACAACGCCUGGCUAAUUUUGUAUUUUUAGUAGAGACUGGUUUCUCCAUGUUGGUCAGGCUGGUCUCAAACUCCCGACCUCAGGUGAUCCGCCCGCCUCGGCCUCCUAAAGUGCUGGGAUUACAGGCGUGAGCCACUGCGCCCAGCUAUACUGUAUAUUUUAAGAAGUUCCAGCAUGUUGCAUCUCUGCAUUUAUCCUAUAUCAUUAAAAGAACAUAAGUUAUCAUGGUGUUGGGUAAAUUAGCGAAAUCAACCCUUCCUAAGUUUAAGGGAAAAGUUAUUUUUAAAAACAACUUAAUAAAAACUUACACUCUUUUAUACAAGAGUGUAUUUCCCCUUAAUUAGGAUGCAUGUUGAUUAAACUCGAGAUACAGCUUUUUGCAGUAUGGUGGGUUGGUUUUGGUGUAACAUCUUCAACAUGUCACACUGGCUAUCAAAGAAUAAGAAAAUUAUUGAGUAUGAGUGUGUUUUAUAAACUUUCUGAGUUUUUCAGAUGUCUUAAUAUUUUUUAAUAGAACUUAAUAAAAUGUCUAGAUUGACUAUUUUC